UCGUCGCUCCCACCUUCCGCUGCCGCCUGGAGGGAAGCCGGAGCGACGGGGGUCACGGCGGCGGUCAGAGGGUAAAGGUCUUGCUCCCAGCAGCCUCCGCGGUGGAUACGUCGCCAUCUUGGAUCCGCGGGACAAGAAAAUUCAUGCGAGGGAGACGUGGUGGGCGGUCCUUCCUGUGACACGACCCUUGAGUGACAGUUCUAUUUGAUUGCCUCCGGUACUGUGAGGAAAGGACACGACUCUAUGGUGAGGACUGAUGGACAUACAUUAUCUGAGAAAAGAAACUACCAGUAAAGACGGGGUUUCACCGUGUUAGCCAGGAUGGUCUCGAUCUCCUGACUUCAUGAUCCGCCUGCCUUGGCCUCCCAAAGUGCUUGGAUUACAGGCGUGAGCCACCGCACCUGGCCGCAAAGUUAUCUUUUAAGAGGUUAUCUUAGGUCUUGCGUGGAGUCUAGGAUGAUAGCACUGAUGGUGGCAGCCUCCAGCUCUGAGCUUUCCAAUCCCCAGAGUAGCAAAUGUUGAAAGAAGUUGCACAGACGUGGUCUCACUCUGUCACCCAGGCUGGACUGCAGUGGCGUCAUCUUGGCUCACUGCAACCUCCGCCUCCCAAGUUCAAGUGAUUCUCCUGCCUCGGCCUCCAAGUAGCUGGGACUACAGGGAGAAGAUGGGUAUAGUUUAACCCUUUCAUAUCAUCCAUCCAUCCAUUCCUACUAGUUCUGCCUCAGAGUAUAUCCUUUAUUCAACUACUACUCACCACCCUAUUAGGCCAUCAUUAUCUAUCACUGGCCUCCUAAUGCAUUUUCCUGCUUUCGUUUUAUACCCUCUUUAGCCCAUUCCUCAUGGAGUAGCUAGGACCUUUAAAAAAAAAAAAAAGCCAAAUUAAGUUACUCUUAAGCUUCGCCUAAAUCCUCUCUUGAUUUCCCGUCUAACAAAGAAUAAAAUCCAAAGUCUCUCAGGCUCUCGAGGUGUACUAUAUGGUCUAGCCCCAACCAGUCUCUCUGACAUGAGUUCCUACCCUUCACCACCUAAGUUCAUGCUGCCUGAGCCAUACCAGUGAGGGGUUUACUGACCCUCUGAACUGACUGCUUUUCCUUCAAGCAUUUGCCUGGUCAGUUACUUCUCUGCUUGUUUUCAUCUCAGUUUUAUGUUCCCUGAUUAUUUUUAAAUACUUCCUACCCUGUUCCAUCAUUCUAUGUAGAAUAAAGGACGGGCACUUUAAAAUUAAAUAAAUCUAGCUUUAUGAAAAACCUGUGUUGUCUUUUUCUCUUGUGAUUUUGCCAUGGAUUAGAAUUGUCUCAUACCAGCACCCAUCUCUGGAUGGGGGUUUGCAUUCAUGGGGGAGAGUAAAACACCCUUACCUCUCCCUCCCUCCAUCUGUCUUUCUCUCUGUCUCACUCUCGUUUUGUUUUUUAAUUAUUUGCUGAAGUCAUGUAAGAAUAAUUAGUAUUGUCACUGAUGUGUAAUUUCUGUGCCAGAGCACACAAAACAGAAAUUAAGCUUAAGUUUGGUAUAUUUUCUCUCUCUCUCUCUCUCUCUCUCUCUCUCACACACACACACACACACACACAGUGACUCUUGAGAAAAUCUGGUAUUGAUGGAAAAGGAACAUUUCUUCAUUUUCUUUCGUCUGGAACAUAUGUUUAAUUUUGCCUUCAAACCAAACCUUUUUGCAAGAUAUUAAGCAUAAAAAUUUUAAUUCUAUACAAUUAAUUUCAAUUUUAGAAUUCUAGGAGUCUAUAAUGGUCUUGAUGAUAAGUGUUAUACAAACAGUGUCAAAAGAAGAGUUUAUCAAUUUGAGCUUAUUUAUGUGUAUAAAAUUUGAUGAGAGAUGCCUUGAUAUUCACCUGAAACUUUAUUGAAUAAUUAUUGAAUUAUGCAUUUUCCAUGUUUAUUCUUUCUUAGAAUUAGAGCUCAAUAGUAAGAGUUCUAUAAAGAUAAUUAAAUGUAUCUUUAACUUUCAAAAAACAAACUUCUAAAAUCUUAUGUGUAGUGAAUCUUAAUUUGCAAGCUCUAAAGUGAUUUUUUGCCACUGUUUCCUUUUUGAAAUUACUCACUAAGAAACAUCUGUUUUCCCCCUAGUAGGGACUACUUAGGGAGCUGGUGGAUAGGCAUGCGGGAUCCUGGUCUGAAAUAACAGAGUUACAGAAUAGCAUUCUGAGAUUCACCAGGAGUCUGUUUCCCAAAAAAAGAUUAAGUACCUGUGUUCUAAUAAAUUGUUAGACCCUUAAAAAAUAUCUUUGUAUAUUUCACACCUCAAGCGAUUACUUGCCUAAAAGCAUAUAGCAAAGUAAUAGGUUAGCUGUCCUUAGACUUUAUUUAUACCUGACUGAAUAGGUUUUCAGACCUCAGGAGGAAAGACAGUCAAAUAAUUAAGUUUCCUACAUAUUUAACAGGGAACUUAAAAUAUAUAAGAAAUAUUAAACAGCAUGGGUGCUUUCAACAGAGUUACACGUAAAGUUUGGCCUUCAAAGUCUGCAACAUAGUUCACCACGUCUACUGAUAUGUAAUAGUGACUACAGCAUUUUUUGAAAUGAGACAUGGAAAUUGUUCACUCAUUUAUAAUGGAAGGAAAUAUUCUUAGUCAUAAUGAAUGUACAAGACAGAUAUCAAAUUUGAGAUGAGUUUUCCCCAAAAAUGUACUUGUGAAAAGACAUAGUCACCUUGUAUUCAAGUCUUUAAAAUCUCUUUUCUCAUUGACAUUGGUUUACCUUGAUUUUCAAAGUACUGUUAGGAGAAAGACACAUUGACCUUAAAUAACUUUAGUCAGUUAAUAGUUUUGAUAAUUUUAUAGAGGUCACAUUUUAAAAAUAAUUAAAAAUUAAAAUUAGCACAGAUUUUAAUAAUUACAGUUGGCCCUUCAUACCCAUGGGUUCUGCAUCUGUGGGUCAACCAGCUGCAGAUUGAAAAUAUUUGGGGAAAAAUAAUGGAUGGUUGUGUCUGUACUGAACAUGUACAGACUGUUUUUUCUUGUAAUUAUUCCCUGAGCAAUACAGUGACUAUUUAUAUAGCAUUUACAUUGUAUUAGAUAUUAUAAGUAAUCUAGAGAUGAUUUAAAGUAUAUGAAAGGAUGUGUGUAGGUUAUAUGCAAAUAUUAUAAACCAUUUUAUGUGAGAGAAUUGAGCAUCCGUGGAUUUUAUUUUUUAAUCCAUGAGGGGAGAGGUCCUAGAACCAUUUCUUCACAGAUAGCAAGUGACAACAAUUUAUGUUGGUGUGAGCUCAAAAUUGCUAAUGUUGGAUGUUACAAAGACUGGAAAAACAAAUGAAUAAGCAGGUUAUAUCAUUGAAAUAAUAACUUUAUACCAGUAUGAUCAAUGAAAGAUUGUACUUCAGUUACAUGAGUGGGUACUUGCUUGAGAUAAAAUUCUAGUAUGCCACUAUAUAUGCACUGAUUCAAAAAACGGUAUAUUUCAGUAAACUUAGAUUGUAAGGAAAGAUGAAUGCUUGGGAAAACAGAUAACUGAGAAAAUAAGGUGAUGACAGAUACACAAAUGUGGAAGAUGCAUGUGAAGAUUUUGAAUAAUUAAACCUAAACUUAAUUUUUAAAAAAUCUAUGUAUGGGAAAAUGAUAUUGGCCAUUUUUGAAGAGUAAGGUAUACUUAGUUUUUUAAAAGGAAAUGGAAUUGUUAAGAUAGGCUUUAUGUGAUUCUCCUACUUUUAGGGUCUGGAAAUAAACAUCUAACACUUUAUUGUUAUAAUCAGAUUUAUGACUUUAUCACAUGCGCCACUAGCCAUUAGUUGAUCAAUUUCUGUAUCUUAGCAAUGCUCCCUUCAUGUUCUGUUUUCCACAUAGGAGUAAGGUAACACUGAACAUUUUCCAAAGUAUUACCCCUGAUAAAAGUAAUAUUUUUGUUUAGGUGACAAACAGCAUGUUUGGUGCUUCAAGAAAGAAGUUUGUAGAGGGGGUCGACAGUGACUACCAUGACGAAAACAUGUACUACAGCCAGUCUUCUAUGUUUCCACAUCGGUCAGAAAAAGAUAUGCUGGCAUCACCAUCUACAUCAGGUCAGCUGUCUCAGUUUGGGGCAAGUUUAUACGGGCAACAAAGUGCACUAGGCCUUCCAAUGAGGGGGAUGAGCAACAAUACCCCUCAGUUAAAUCGCAGCUUAUCACAAGGCACUCAGUUACCGAGCCACGUCACGCCAACAACAGGGGUACCAACAAUGUCACUUCACACGCCUCCAUCUCCAAGCAGGGGUAUUUUGCCUAUGAAUCCUAGGAAUAUGAUGAACCACUCCCAGGUUGGUCAGGGCAUUGGAAUUCCUAGCAGGACAAAUAGCAUGAGCAGUUCAGGGUUAGGUAGCCCCAACAGAAGCUCGCCAAGCAUAAUAUGUAUGCCAAAGCAGCAGCCUUCUCGACAGCCUUUUACUGUGAACAGUAUGUCUGGAUUUGGAAUGAACAGGAAUCAGGCAUUUGGAAUGAAUAACUCCUUAUCAAGUAACAUUUUUAAUGGAACAGACGGAAGUGAAAAUGUGACAGGAUUGGACCUUUCAGAUUUCCCAGCAUUAGCAGACCGAAACAGGAGGGAAGGAAGUGGUAACCCAACUCCAUUAAUAAACCCCUUGGCUGGAAGAGCUCCUUAUGUUGGAAUGGUAACAAAACCAGCAAAUGAACAAUCCCAGGACUUCUCAAUACACAAUGAAGAUUUUCCAGCAUUACCAGGCUCCAGCUAUAAAGAUCCAACAUCAAGUAAUGAUGACAGUAAAUCUAAUUUGAAUACAUCUGGCAAGACAACUUCAAGUACAGAUGGACCCAAAUUCCCUGGAGAUAAAAGUUCAACAACACAAAAUAAUAACCAGCAGAAAAAAGGGAUCCAGGUGUUACCUGAUGGUCGGGUUACUAACAUUCCUCAAGGGAUGGUGACGGACCAAUUUGGAAUGAUUGGCCUGUUAACAUUUAUCAGGGCAGCAGAGACAGACCCAGGAAUGGUACAUCUUGCAUUAGGAAGUGACUUAACAACAUUAGGCCUCAAUCUGAACUCUCCUGAAAAUCUCUACCCCAAAUUUGCGUCACCCUGGGCAUCUUCACCUUGUCGACCUCAAGACAUAGACUUCCAUGUUCCAUCUGAGUACUUAACGAACAUUCACAUUAGGGAUAAGCUGGCUGCAAUAAAACUUGGCCGAUAUGGUGAAGACCUUCUCUUCUAUCUCUAUUACAUGAAUGGAGGAGACGUAUUACAACUUUUAGCUGCAGUGGAGCUUUUUAACCGUGAUUGGAGAUACCACAAAGAAGAACGAGUAUGGAUUACCAGGGCACCAGGCAUGGAGCCAACAAUGAAAACCAAUACCUAUGAGAGGGGAACAUAUUACUUCUUUGACUGUCUUAACUGGAGGAAAGUAGCUAAGGAGUUCCAUCUGGAAUAUGACAAAUUAGAAGAACGGCCUCACCUGCCAUCCACCUUCAACUACAACCCUGCUCAGCAAGCCUUCUAAAAAAAAAAAAAAAAAAAAAAAAAGACUUCCCUUUUCUUGGGGUAUGGCUGUCUCAGCACAAUACUCAACAUAACUGCAGAACUGAUGUGGCUCAGGCACCCUGGUUUUAAUUCCUUGAGGAUCUGGCAAUUGGCUUACGCAAAAGGUCACCAUUUGAGGUCCUGCCUUACUAAUUAUGUGCUGCCCAACAACUAAAUUUGUAAUUUGUUUUUCUCUAGUUUGAGCAGGGUCUGAAUUUUUUCAUUUAUUUCCUUUUUUGCCAGCAGACAGACUUGAGUCUGUAAAGACAAGCAAAUACACUGACAGAAGUUUACCAUAGUUUCUAAAAUGUAAAAAAGAAAACCCCCAAAAGACUCAAGAAAAUUAGACCACAAAUUUUGCAUUGUUCAUUGUAGCACUAUUGGUAAUAAAAUAACAAAUGUUUGUGCAUUUUUAUGUGAAGAUCCUUCUCGUAUUUCAUUUGGAAAGAUGAGCAAGAGGUCUGCUUCCUUCAUUUUACUUCCCCUUCUGUUUUUGAAAGGCAGUUUCGCCAAGCUUAAUGCAAGAAUAUCUGACUGUUUAGAAGAAAGAUAUUGCCACAAUCUCUGGAUGGUUUUCCAGGGUUGUGUUAUUACUGAGCUUCAUCUUUCCAGAAUGAGCAAAACACUGUCCAGUCUUUGUUACGAUUUUGUAAUAAAUGUGUACAUUUUUUUUAAAUUUUUGGACAUCACAUGAAUAAAGGUAUGUAUGUACGAAUGUGUAUAUAUUAUAUAUAUGACAUCUAUUUUGGAAAAUGUUUGCCCUGCUGUACCUCAUUUUUAGGAGGUGUGCAUGGAUGCAAUAUAUGAAAAUGGGACAUUCUGGAACUGCUGGUCAGGGGACUUUGUCGCCCUGUGCACUAAAAGGGCCAGAUUUUCAGCAGCCAAGGACAUCCAUACCCAAGUGAAUGUGAUGGGACUUAAAAGAAGUGAACUGAGACAAUUCACUCUGGCUGUUUGAACAGCAGCGUUUCAUAGGAAGAGAAAAAAAGAUCAAUCUUGUAUUUUCUGACCACAUAAAGGCUUCUUCUCUUUGUAAUAAAGUAGAAAAGCUCUCCUCA